AACUCUUCCCUCUUUGGUUCCUGGAGCUGUGUGCACAGUGCUGAAGUAUGACAUCCAUGCCUUCAGUUAAGUGGUCAUCUUCAAAUACCUCUAACUGGCACUCUCUUUUUUUUUUUGAAGCUUUUGCCUUUUAACCUGGAUCUCCUCUCAUCUUUUCAAGGAAAGAUACUAAUAUGAAGACAGAAAAAAAGAAGAUCAAGAAGGUUCCCUUUUAUCUCUUGUUUCUAAGGUCUCACCUCUUGUGAAGUUGUUUGUAAACAAUUUUGUCUUUACCUAAUAUUCCUCUCUCUGGAUAUAUUAUACCUGUAACUCCUUCUGAUUCAUCAGGUCCUCACGAGGAGCUCGUUAGAUGAGAUGCUACCCAUUAGAUGGAGGAUCUGCAUUUUGGGUGGACAGUGGACAGAAUAAAUCUUCAGCCCGUUUUUCCCCUCACCACCUGAUCCACUCAGCCUCUUCUAAACCGUACCAUGAAUGAAAACAAUGAAACCUUGACCAGAGGCUUUACCCUCAUGGGGCUCUUCACUCACAAUAAAUGCUCAGGAUUCUUUUUCGGUGUCAUUUGUGCCGUCUUCUUCAUGGCCAUGAUAGCUAAUGGGGUCAUGAUCUUCCUGAUUAACAUAGACCCUCAUCUCCACACCCCCAUGUACUUCCUCCUCAGCCACCUCUCCGUCAUUGACACAUUAUACAUCUCCACCAUUGUGCCCAAGAUGCUGGUAGAUUAUCUCAUGGGCGAGGGGACCAUCUCUUUCAUCGCCUGCACUGCUCAGUGCUUUCUCUACAUGGGCUUUAUGGGGGCUGAAUUCUUCCUGCUGGGGCUCAUGGCCUAUGACCGCUACGUGGCCAUCUGCAACCCACUGCGCUAUCCUGUCCUCAUCAGCUGGCGGGUCUGCUGGAUGAUCCUGGCCAGCUCUUGGUUCGGUGGGGCUUUGGACAGUUUUCUCCUCACCCCCAUUACCAUGAGUCUCCCGUUCUGUGCCUCUCACCAAAUCAAUCACUUUUUCUGUGAGGCACCCACCAUGCUGAGGCUGGCCUGUGGGGACAAAACCACCUAUGAAACAGUGAUGUAUGUGUGCUGCGUUGCAAUGCUGCUGAUCCCCUUCUCGGUGGUGACUGCAUCCUACACCAGGAUUCUCAUCACAGUGCAUCAGAUGACAUCGGCUGAAGGGAGGAAGAAGGCCUUUGCCACCUGCUCUUCACACAUGAUGGUGGUGACAUUGUUCUAUGGGGCUGCCUUGUAUACGUAUACGCUUCCCCAAUCUUACCACACCCCAAUCAAAGAUAAGGUCUUCUCUGCCUUUUAUACCAUCCUCACACCCUUAUUAAACCCUCUCAUCUACAGUCUGAGGAACAGGGAUGUGAUGGGUGCCUUGAAGAGAGUUGUGGCAAGAUGUUAGGGGACAUGUGGUGUGAUGAGGAAAGAAUUCUGAUGGUCUAAAACCUCCACAUCCUGUUCAGGCAUAUAUGGGGUCGUAUCAUGGAUACCACGGAUGAUGCUGACAGGAACUUUCAAUACCAGCUGUGCUAAAUGGUGUAUCAACAGUACCCCCAUCAAAAAUGGGAAGUUGCUGUAACAGUCACACACAAAUAAUGCCAGAGUUCUAGAAACACCACUCAUGUUUAUUCUUCUUUUGUUUCUACUGAUUCCAAGUCUUCUCUCAUAUCACUUCUCUGAUUGCAGUUUGUGUAUAUGAAUGCCCCAAAAUGUUGAGUUAAUAUUACAUAUUCUGCCCAUUUUCAAUGGCUCCAUAAGAACUGGUGAUUUUGACUAUAUUGUUUAAACAAUCCAUCAAUUGGCUUGUCAAAGAUUUAGGGAUGCCAAGGUUUGAAAGACAUAUGAAAGAGACUAAACUGUCAUAAAACUGUAAAAGAAAAAUCUACAUAGACUUACACCAAGAUUUAGAAAAUCCAAAUAUCUCUUCUUUGAGUAACCACUGAAAACACUCCUCCUUUAUCUACAUUUGGAGCUAAAAAAAAAUGAAUCAUGUGUUUUGUAGAAAUGCCAAGACUAAAUCUUUAUGGGGGAGGGAGUCUGUAAUGUUAGUUUUUUAAUAUGGUAACUAACUGUUACAUUGGAAGACACAGCAAAAGGUAGUUGAGAAAGAAAUGCCCUAUUAACUAGCAGUUUCUGUAAUCACUUUACAGCUUCUUCUCCAAUUCACUAGCAUUUUUAAACUUUUGGGAUCCCUGUGCAGAUGUUAGUGUUGUUGGAGCUAUUUCUACCAACUUUUCUCUUUUAAAAAAGUAGUAGACAGCGUCAUAUUUUUCCUUCUCUAUAGCACUGGCUUUUGCAUUGGAUAGCAUUGCAAAGUGGGAAGGAAAUACCCAGCUUUUCAUGUGAAAAUUAGAACUGGAAACCCUUGUAAAUGACUUAGUGUCAUGAGCGGUGCAAAGUUAGAAAUAACCAGGACCACAAAUGCUUGUGUCUUUCCACAAUGUCAGGAUUUUAUUGAUGCUGUUUCAAUCACAAAAGCCACCAUGAGCUACAUAGAGUUCCCAAGGGGGCAACUCUCCUUAGUACUUUUCAUUCACUUGGUAGUCAGCGUUGUGGGCACACAGACUCAAGCCACUCCACAAGUCAGUCAAUAUUGCAAACCAUACAUAAUAGUAUACUUAAUCAAUAUGUAAAUGUUAUAGGUUUAACAUUUCACAACAAACAAACUAACAUUUAACACAAGAAGGAAAAGGGAUAGGAGAAAGGAUCACAAACCAGUCCAAGGGGAGAGAAGAAGAGAAAAGCGGUCCUGGUCCAGGCCGGGUGGUCCACUGGUCUUGCAAGAAAGAGUCUCUGAGGUGGCAGAGACUUCAGCAGCAGAUGCCAAGUUUUCAUCACCAGUGACUGCAAGAUGGCAUCAGUUAACAUGGCUAUUUCGAGCUGCUGAAGGCCUGCUCUUUUACGGUUACAGAGUCCUCCCAUGAGAACUGAUCAUGGAAGAGUGUGCUUGUUUGAGUCCUUAUCUGGUUGGAUACAGUCUUUUAUUUUUUAAUUUGUUUAGUAGACAACACAUCUUAUCCUUGUUGGAAAAGUGCUCUAUGAAAUAUAAAAUAAAGUCUUUUUCUAAGAUGGAGUUGGCUACGUCAAGGGUGUUCUAUACACUUAGUAUGAUUUCUUUUUAAGUGGCUAAGAACUGGAGAAAAAAUGUUUGGCCUAAACUGUAGACACAGUAGUAAAAACCAGGACCACAUCCCAAACCCCUCAGGCCACCUCUACAAGCUGCUGUGCCAGGCUUUGUACUGUCAUUGGUUUAACAAAAUCCAAGCCGGGUUCAGUGACGUUCUGCAGCGACUGAAGAUGGUGGGUGAAUGAAAGAUAGCCACACCUCCUUUUGUACUGAAAAAAGCUGCUGGGUAUUUGACAAAAUAUUUAGCCAAAUAGAACAGCUCAACUUGGCAUUGGGCUGAGCACUUAAUCAAGAAAAUAGACCAGGUCUUGCCUAACAGAGCAGGGUUUUCAGUUGAAAUCCAGGAACAGCUUUUCCGAGGCUCUUCAGCUGGAGGCUCAACAUCUCCUCAAUCUUGUCAGACUGUCUUGGACAACAGUAUGUGCCAGAUAAUAUGAGGGAGCAUUUCCAACCAAGAAGAUGUUGAGGUACAAAAAACACAACAAAUCAGAAGAGAAGGAGAGGGCUGGCCCAUAAGAACUGAUCAUCAGUUUCAGCUCCACGUAAACACCAUGUGAAUUUCUGUCAAUCAUACAAUGCUUCUGAGGACCAACUUUCUUUUUUAUAAAAUUUGACUUAAUACAUACUUUUUUUCUUGUAAGAUUUUAAAAUCAAGUAAAAUGAUGAAUGUAAUAAAACCUUAUAAAUGCUAGUCAUUAUUUCAGCUAUUCUUUGAAAAGAUGAUUGACUUUUAUAUUCAGUUUUUACAAUUUCUUUCAUUUCUAUCGAUCCGUUACAGACAAAAGCACACUCUCUUGUACAGCCACUUUGGAAUACAGUUUGACAGUUUCUUACAAUAUUGAACAUAAUCUUAUCAUAUGAUCUGGCAAUUGUGUUUCUUGGUGUUAACUCUGCUGAUUUGGAAACUUAUGUUCACAGUAGAUUUUUCAUACAUUCCAAAACAUAGACUUAAUCAGAAAGUCCUUCAGAAAUUAAAUGGAUAAAGUGUGGCACAUGCAUACAGUGGAAUAUUAUUUAGUGUUAAAAAUAAAUGAUUUAUCAAGCCAUUGGAAGACAUGGAGGAAAUUUAAAUGUAUAUUGUGAAGUGAAAGAAGCCAAUCUGAAAAGGCUGCAUACUGUGUGAUUCCAGCUGCAUGACAUCCUGGAAAAAACAAAACUGUGGAUACAGGAAAAAGAUAAGUGUUGCAAGGGGUCUGGGGGAAGUAUGGAUGGAUGGACAGAGCACAGAGGACUUUUAGAGCAGUGAAACUAUUGUAUAUGACACAGUAAUUAAUGUUACAUAAGAUUAUGCUACAUGGUACUAUGUAUUUGUGGAAAAAAACAUACAACUCUGGAACAGAAAGACUCAUCCUUAUGUAAAAUAUGAACUAUUAAUAAUAAUGUAUCAAAAUUGAUUCAUCUAUUGUAACAAAUGUACUACACUAAUGCCAGAUGUUAACAAUAGGGAAAAGAGAGGGGAUAUAUAAAAACUUUCUGAACUAUCCAUUCAAUUUUUUGGUAAACCUCAUUGUUCUAAAAUAUAAAAUUUCAUUUUAAAACAGUUUUCUAACA